ACAGAGAGGCUGGGAGAGCAAGCCGGAGAGAAGAGAGAGCCCGGCCAGACCCACUGCGAUGAGACAGCAGGACGCGCCCAAGCCCACUCCUGCAGCCUGCCGCUGCUCCGGCCUGGCCCGGAGGGUGCUGACCAUCGCCUUCGCCCUGCUCAUCCUGGGCCUCAUGACCUGGGCCUACGCCGCCGGGGUGCCGCUGGCCUCCGAUCGCUACGGCCUCCUGGCCUUCGGCCUCUACGGGGCCUUCCUUUCAGCGCACCUGGUGGCGCAGAGCCUCUUCGCGUACCUGGAGCACCGGCGGGUGGCGGCGGCGGCGCGGGGGCCGCUGGAUGCAGCCACCGCGCGCAGUGUGGCGCUGACCAUCUCCGCCUACCAGGAGGACCCCGCGUACCUGCGCCAGUGCCUGGCGUCCGCCCGCGCCCUGCUGUACCCGCGCGCGCGGCUGCGCGUCCUCAUGGUGGUGGAUGGCAACCGCGCCGAGGACCUCUACAUGGUCGACAUGUUCCGCGAGGUCUUCGCUGACGAGGACCCCGCCACGUACGUGUGGGACGGCAACUACCACCAGCCCUGGGAACCCGCGGCGGCGGGCGCGGUGGGCGCCGGAGCCUAUCGGGAGGUGGAGGCGGAGGAUCCUGGGCGGCUGGCAGUGGAGGCGCUGGUGAGGACUCGCAGGUGCGUGUGCGUGGCGCAGCGCUGGGGCGGCAAGCGCGAGGUCAUGUACACAGCCUUCAAGGCGCUCGGAGAUUCGGUGGACUACGUGCAGGUCUGUGACUCGGACACAAGGUUGGACCCCAUGGCACUGCUGGAGCUCGUGCGGGUACUGGACGAGGACCCCCGGGUAGGGGCUGUUGGUGGGGACGUGCGGAUCCUUAACCCUCUGGACUCCUGGGUCAGCUUCCUAAGCAGCCUGCGAUACUGGGUAGCCUUCAAUGUGGAGCGGGCUUGUCAGAGCUACUUCCACUGUGUAUCCUGCAUCAGCGGUCCUCUAGGCCUAUAUAGGAAUAACCUCUUGCAGCAGUUUCUUGAGGCCUGGUACAACCAGAAGUUCCUGGGUACCCACUGUACUUUUGGGGAUGACCGGCACCUCACCAACCGCAUGCUCAGCAUGGGUUAUGCUACCAAGUACACCUCCAGGUCCCGCUGCUACUCAGAGACGCCCUCGUCCUUCCUGCGGUGGCUGAGCCAGCAGACACGCUGGUCCAAGUCGUACUUCCGUGAGUGGCUGUACAACGCGCUCUGGUGGCACCGGCACCAUGCGUGGAUGACCUACGAGGCGGUGGUCUCCGGCCUGUUCCCCUUCUUCGUGGCGGCCACUGUGCUGCGUCUGUUCUACGCGGGCCGCCCUUGGGCGCUGCUGUGGGUGCUGCUGUGCGUGCAGGGCGUGGCACUGGCCAAGGCGGCCUUCGCGGCCUGGCUGCGGGGCUGCCUGCGCAUGGUGCUUCUGUCGCUCUACGCGCCCCUCUACAUGUGUGGCCUCCUGCCUGCCAAGUUCCUGGCGCUAGUCACCAUGAACCAGAGUGGCUGGGGCACCUCGGGCCGGCGGAAGCUGGCCGCUAACUACGUCCCUCUGCUGCCCCUGGCGCUCUGGGCGCUGCUGCUGCUUGGGGGCCUGGUCCGCAGCGUAGCACACGAGGCCAGGGCCGACUGGAGCGGCCCUUCCCGCGCAGCCGAGGCCUACCACUUGGCCGCGGGGGCCGGCGCCUACGUGGGCUACUGGGUGGCCAUGUUGACGCUGUACUGGGUGGGCGUGCGGAGGCUUUGCCGGCGGCGGACCGGGGGCUACCGCGUCCAGGUGUGAGUCCAGCCACGCGGAUGCCGCCUCAAGGGUCUUCAGGGGAGGCCAGAGGAGAGCUGCUGGGCCCCGAGCCACGAACUUGCUGGGUGGUUCUCUGGGCCUCAGUUUCCCUCCUCUGCAAAACGAGGGGGUCAGCCCAAGAUUCUUCAGUCUGGACUAUAUUGGGACUGGGACUUCUGGGUCUCCAGGGAGGGUAUUUAUUGGUCAGGGUGUGGGAUCUGAGGAGUGGAGGGAAAGGGUCCUGCUUUCUCCUCGUUCUUAUUUAAUCUCCAUUUCUACUGUGUGAUCAGGAUGUAAUAAAGAAUUUUAUUUAUUUUC